CGGGCUUCCUUUUAAUCUGUAGCUCUGGAAUACUCUUGCUAUUGAUGAUUCUAUGUGUCGACUAUUUUGCUCACACCCCACCCAGAUGCAUUCUCUACUGUGGUUCUCUGCUCUUCCCUGUGCCAGGGGAAGCUGAUGGCUCCUUUGCUGGCAGGGCUCCAGUUGGGUUUGGUCAAUGGGAGGGACUGACAGGAGACUGGAAGUGGAAGGAGAGAGAGGUUGGUAGAAUUCUUUUCUACUUCCCCUUGCUUCCAUGCUGUCUGGAGGCGGUGGCAUGCCUCCACACUACAGAAGCUCCCACUGGGGGCCCUUCCUCUGCAGUCCUCUGGCUGUGGUAAUGUGGUUUUCUCCUUUUGUUCUUUUAACUGUAGGGUGGUGAUUGCUUCUGUCUUCUGCCAGUCUCUGGGUGCCUCACCAUUUCUUGUUUCUUUCCUUUAAUGCUUCCCACACCUCUGUAAGUUACCUUUUUAUUAAAAUCCCUUUGUUUGACAAUCUGGGGGUGAAUUAUGUGUCCUGUGCAGACUAUGACUGAUAUGCUGCCUUUCAUUGUCUUGAUUUUUCCUUCCUGGAAAUUUUAGUAAUUGGAUGAUGGGUCAUUAGUGUUAAUCAUCCAUGUCUCUUAUUUUAGCUCUGAAGUUUUCCAUCUUUCUGUGUUUUUGCUCUACAUUAUGGGAUAUUUCCUAAGCUGGUUCUCCCAUCCCUUCUAAUGAUGUGUUUUCAAAUUUCAGUAGUCAUGCUUAGUUUUCAAGGAUUCUUUCUUGCUUUCUUAGUCUGUCUUAUUUCAUGGCAAUCUGCUCUUGUUAUAUGGAUUCAGUAAUUUCUCUAAUUUAGGCAUUAAAGGAAGUUUUGGUCUCUUAAAGUUAUUUUCUAUUCCCUAAGUUAUUUCAGCUUCUUUUGGGGUCAGUUAUUUUGUUUAUUCAUCUUGACCUAUCUCCUUUGUGCUGUUGAUUUCCUAAAUGUGUGAGGAUCUUUGCUUCUCUGUUAUAAGUACUGGAAAAUAAACUGGUUUCCCCGGAUAGCUGAUGUGGCUUCCCUCUGCUACAGCCUUCCAUGAAAAAAGUAGGACAGCUUCCGGGAGCUAGCUAUAUGUGAGUGGACCAUGCUUGGCAGCUGCCCUUCAGAAUGCACAGGUUGCGGGCAGGGAUGGCCAAGGACAUUUCUCAGGGAGCUGUGUGUGUGGGAUGGGUCUCUGAGAAUGGAGAGCUUGAUGAGUUCAGGCCGUGGAAGCAACAUCUACACAAGCCUGGAUCUGAGAAACUCAACCAUACUCCCUGAAAAUGGAGAGUUUACAUGCAGAAUGAGUCUGGGGGAGGCAGCACUAGAAGGCCUGAAAGAGGAAGAGAGUCAGACUGAUUUCAGAGGGACCCAUCCUAGAGGGACCACUGCCAUGACUCCAUGGGGACAUUUCCAAGGGGAGCCACAGGAGGUUUCACUGGAGAGUUGUGUAUGUCUGUCCAGUGUCUAGGAGGUGCUCACCAUGGCUGAGCUUGCAGGGCCUCUUAGGACUGUCCAGGUGAGAUGUGUGGGUCGUGAUGAGGGUUUGGAGAGGUUUCCAGCUAGAAUUGGUCGGGACAGCCCAUUAGCUCUGGGGCAGAGGCUCAGGGAGGUGGGCAAGCAUGCAGGACACAGGAAUGCUUAUAGCCACAGCUCUGCAGGGUGUUUCUUGCCCAUAACUGUGUGGAGAGCCAUUCUCAUCUCAACUCAUUUCUUGCCACAACAUCUCCCGAGGCAAACUUUGUUAUUAGCUCCGCUUUGCAGAUGAGAAUCUGGGGCAAUGCGAGACGGCUUCUGUGCCCGGCUUGUGACCAGUCACCACACUGACUCUCAAUGUGGUGUAAGCAACUGUGAAUGGGCCUGAUUCCAAAUCCCAGCAAAUUUACAGUAAGGAGGGUGCCUGGGGUCUAUCCAUCCCCUGACUAGCUGAUCUUCAGCUUCCUCAUAGGACCAGGGGGAAUACUGAGCAUGCAGUGGACUGAGGUUCAGAGAGGUAAUGUGGAGCGCUGCACACACCUGAGGGAGUUGUGCGCCUGUCUGACUUCCGGGUGAUUCAUGAGGAACAUUCCUGAUGGGGUGGGAAGGGAACCUGUCACUAAGCUAUUUAGGAGAAGCAGUCUCCAGCAGGUCACACCAGCCAGCCACUUUUAUGGCAGAAGGAAAAUCCUACCUAGCCCCUUCCCCAGAGAUGGCAGAAUGCAGCCUGGCUGACUGGCAGAGCCUCUCAGGCUGUGCUCCGGACCCUGGACUCCAGCAAGGGGGAAGAACAGCAGCUCCCAGUUCUUUCUUACAGACUGCUUUCUUGAGGAGCUUCAAGUGCUCUGGCUAUGAUUGGUGCAGGGCUCUGCUGCCUCCAGAGGGUGCUGUCUCCUUUCCCUAGCAGAGGCAAAGGGUCUGGCAGCCAACUCUGGGAGUAUUGGUUUAACCUGAAAUGUCUGCUAGGAAGAGCUACCUACCCCUCUCCUGGGCAUUAUGGUCCUGAAGGAAGAGCUUGGACUUUGGAUUGAAAGUCCAGCCCUACCAUCUACAAGUUGGCUGGCUGAGACAAGACACUCUACUUCUUUGAGGCUCAGUUUUCUCGCCUGUGAGAUGGGAUGAUCACACCACACCAGUUAGGCAUGAGGAUGGACUAAGGGCAUGUUCACAUGCUUCUGCCUGGCAAGGGAGCUGUUUGCUGCUUUUACCACCAUUUCAGCUCUUCUGCUGUUCUCUGACCCACAAGAGCUAGGGUUCAGGCUGCGUGCCUUGCGCAGUAGUUCUCAAAUGUGUCUAUGUGGAAGCUUGCCUCCAAGGGCUUACCAGCAAAUCCAGACCCCACACAGCUGCCCUGCAAGAAGGAGGUGACAGUGGCUGCGUUCUUGCCUGCACAGAGGACGGGUGUCCAUAGAGCUCCCAGCUGGAGUUGAGCAGUUUCUGGUCAAGCAAUGUUCUCUGAUUUUACAUGUCUGGAAGCUACCGUUACAAUCAGGUCUUCUUAAAUGUCCUCCCUCCCUCCGUCUUCCUUUCUUCCUUUCUUUCUUUGUCAGAUGCUGUGUGUGGACUUGUGCUGGGAUCUGGAGGCGGAGACAAGAGCUGUGACCUAGACAUAGGGGAGUGGGGAGACAAAGCUGCUCAGGCAGACAACCAACUAGGCUGCUACAUCUGCUUCUGCAGCAGAGCAUGGGAGGGUGGUAGGAAUUUGUCAUGGCAGCAGGGACAUCGGAGCUGGGGUGCAACGGAGGAGCAGCCGCUUUCCAGGUAGUCAAGACAGGAAGGAGCAUGGUCCAGAAAGAAGAGAUGACAGGUGCCAGUCUACAGCGAUGGCGUCAUCCCUCAAGUGUAUCACUUAGUUCAAGAGUCCUGGAAUCUUUUCACAUCCACUAUGAACACCUCUCACCUCCUGGCCUUGCUGCUCCCAAAAUCUCCACAAGGUGAAAACAGAAGCAAACCCCUGGGCACCCCAUACAACUUCUCUGAACAUUGCCAGGAUUCCGUGGACGUGAUGGUCUUCAUCGUCACUUCCUACAGCAUUGAGACUGUCGUGGGGGUCCUGGGUAACCUCUGCCUGAUGUGUGUGACUGUGAGGCAGAAGGAGAAAGCCAACGUGACCAACCUGCUUAUCGCCAACCUGGCCUUCUCUGACUUCCUCAUGUGCCUCCUCUGCCAGCCGCUGACCGCCGUCUACACCAUCAUGGACUACUGGAUCUUUGGAGAGACCCUCUGCAAGAUGUCGGCCUUCAUCCAGUGCAUGUCGGUGACGGUCUCCAUCCUCUCGCUCGUCCUCGUGGCCCUGGAGAGGCAUCAGCUCAUCAUCAACCCAACAGGCUGGAAGCCCAGCAUCUCACAGGCCUACCUGGGGAUUGUGCUCAUCUGGGUCAUUGCCUGUGUCCUCUCCCUGCCCUUCCUGGCCAACAGCAUCCUGGAGAAUGUCUUCCACAAGAACCACUCCAAGGCUCUGGAGUUCCUGGCGGAUAAGGUGGUCUGUACCGAGUCCUGGCCACUGGCUCACCACCGCACCAUCUACACCACCUUCCUGCUCCUCUUCCAGUACUGCCUCCCACUGGGCUUCAUCUUGGUCUGUUAUGCACGCAUCUACCGGUGCCUGCAGAGGCAGGGGCGCGUGUUUCACAAGGGCACCUACAGCUUGCGAGCUGGGCACAUGAAGCAGGUCAAUGUGGUGCUGGUGGUGAUGGUGGUGGCCUUUGCCGUGCUCUGGCUGCCUCUGCAUGUGUUCAACAGCCUGGAAGACUGGCACCAUGAGGCCAUCCCCAUCUGCCAUGGGAACCUCAUCUUCUUAGUGUGCCACUUGCUUGCCAUGGCCUCCACCUGUGUCAACCCAUUCAUCUAUGGCUUUCUCAACACCAACUUCAAGAAGGAGAUCAAGGCCCUGGUGCUGACUUGCCAGCAGAGCGCCCCCCUGGAGGAGUCAGAGCAUCUGCCCCUGUCCACAGUACAUACGGAAGUCUCCAAAGGGUCCCUGAGGCUAAGUGGCAGGUCCAAUCCCAUUUAACCAGGUCUAGGUCUUCUCCCUGCCAUGUCCCUUGCCAGGCUCUUCCACUUAGCUAAGUGGGCACACUGCAAGCUGGGGUGGCACCCCAGCAUUCCUGGCUUUCUGGGGUCCAGAUAGGCUGGCAAGAGCUGUUUUUGCAUCCAUUUGCAUCGUGAAGACUGGCAUUUUGAUACUUCAGCUGUUUGUUCCUGGGAGAAUUCUGAGCACAGAUUCCAGAGGUCACAGUAAGCCUUGCAGCUUGAGCUGAAAGAUGCCAGAGCCGGAGAUGUCUGCUGGCAGCAGGCAGGGUUCAUUCUGGUGACACAGCAACAGAUGCCUGGCCUGGGAACCCAGGGAUUUCACCUCCACCAGUGAGACCACGGGGCCACUGUGGGGUGAGGGAAGGAGCGCUUGGAGUCAGAGCUCUAGA